GUUGGUCUCCAUGGCGAUGCUGACCGCCUGCGCUUCAGCGCCUAAUUGACAGGAAGGGUCGGCGCUGGGCUUUUAAUUGUGGGGGCUUGCUGGGCCUGCGCAGUUGUGGGCAGGGGGCUGGUGCGGGGAGCGGGUUACGCGCGUCCAGGGGAGGGUGGGGGCGUUUGUGUUGACACCGCCCGGCCACGUUACAAUGGAGAUACUGUCUCUGACCUCAUGGGCCAGUUUGGAAAAAGAUUACUGAGUUGGAGCCGUCUCAAAUUUGCAGGGAGGGACGGGGUGGGGGGUGGGGGGACCCCGGUUGUGCAGUUUGAUAUUGAGGGAGCCCCCACCUACUCGCUGGGGCUGCGUAAUCUGGACGUUUCCAAACUGAAGCGAAGGCGUCGGGAGACUAGGCCUCAGAGAACCAUGGCUACUGCCAAGGGAAUCGCCAUAGGCAUCGACCUGGGCACCACCUACUCCUGUGUGGGGGUGUUCCAGCACGGCAAGGUGGAGAUCAUCGCCAACGACCAGGGCAACCGCACCACCCCCAGCUACGUGGCCUUCACAGACACCGAGCGGCUCAUUGGGGAUGCGGCCAAGAACCAGGUAGCAAUGAAUCCCCAGAACACUGUUUUUGAUGCUAAACGUCUGAUCGGCAGGAAAUUUAAUGAUCCUGUUGUACAAGCAGAUAUGAAACUUUGGCCUUUUCAAGUGAUUAAUGAAGGAGGCAAGCCCAAAGUCCUUGUGUCCUACAAAGGGGAGAAUAAAGCUUUCUACCCUGAGGAAAUCUCUUCGAUGGUAUUGACUAAGUUGAAGGAGACUGCUGAGGCCUUUUUGGGCCACCCUGUCACCAAUGCAGUGAUUACCGUGCCAGCCUAUUUCAAUGACUCUCAACGUCAGGCUACUAAGGAUGCAGGUGUGAUUGCUGGACUUAAUGUGCUAAGAAUCAUCAAUGAGCCCACGGCUGCUGCCAUUGCCUAUGGUUUAGAUAAAGGAGGUCAAGGAGAACGACAUGUCCUGAUUUUUGAUCUGGGUGGAGGCACAUUUGAUGUGUCAAUUCUGACCAUAGAUGAUGGGAUUUUUGAGGUAAAGGCCACUGCUGGGGACACUCACCUGGGUGGGGAGGACUUUGACAACAGGCUUGUGAGCCACUUCGUGGAGGAGUUCAAGAGGAAACACAAAAAGGACAUCAGCCAGAACAAGCGAGCCGUGAGGCGGCUGCGCACCGCCUGCGAGAGGGCCAAGAGGACCCUGUCGUCCAGCACCCAGGCCAACCUAGAAAUUGAUUCACUUUAUGAAGGCAUUGACUUCUAUACAUCCAUCACCAGAGCUCGAUUUGAAGAGUUGUGUGCAGACCUGUUUAGGGGUACCCUGGAGCCUGUAGAAAAAGCGCUUCGGGAUGCCAAGAUGGAUAAGGCUAAAAUCCAUGACAUUGUUUUAGUAGGGGGCUCCACCCGCAUCCCCAAGGUGCAGCGGCUGCUUCAGGACUACUUCAAUGGACGUGAUCUCAACAAGAGCAUCAACCCUGAUGAGGCCGUAGCAUAUGGGGCUGCGGUACAAGCAGCCAUCCUGAUGGGGGACAAGUCUGAGAAGGUACAGGACCUGCUGCUGCUGGACGUGGCUCCCCUGUCCCUGGGGCUGGAGACGGCUGGGGGCGUGAUGACUGCCCUGAUAAAGCGCAACUCCACCAUCCCCACCAAGCAGACACAGAUUUUCACCACCUACUCUGACAACCAACCCGGGGUGCUGAUCCAGGUGUAUGAGGGCGAGAGGGCCAUGACAAAGGACAACAACCUGCUGGGGCGGUUUGACCUGACUGGAAUCCCUCCAGCACCCAGGGGAGUUCCUCAGAUCGAGGUGACGUUUGACAUUGAUGCCAAUGGUAUUCUCAAUGUCACAGCCACGGACAAGAGCACCGGCAAGGUGAACAAGAUCACCAUCACCAAUGACAAGGGCCGCCUGAGCAAGGAGGAGAUUGAGCGCAUGGUUCUGGAUGCUGAGAAAUAUAAAGCUGAAGAUGAGGUCCAGAGGGAGAAAAUUGCUGCAAAGAAUGCCUUAGAAUCCUAUGCUUUUAACAUGAAGAGUGUUGUGAGUGAUGAAGGUUUGAAGGGCAAGAUUAGUGAGUCUGAUAAAAAUAAAAUAUUGGAUAAAUGCAACGAGCUCCUUUCGUGGCUGGAGGUCAAUCAACUGGCAGAGAAAGAUGAGUUUGAUCAUAAGAGAAAGGAAUUGGAGCAGAUGUGUAACCCUAUCAUCACAAAACUCUACCAAGGAGGAUGCACUGGGCCUGCCUGCGGAACAGGGUAUGUGCCUGGAAGGCCUGCCACAGGCCCCACAAUUGAAGAAGUAGAUUAAUUCUUUUUAGAACUGAAGCAUCCUAGGAUGCCUCUACAUGUAUUUCAUUCCCCUCAUCUUCAAACAUCAUUAUUAUUCUUGACCAGACCUGAAUCUAAGUUACCAUCCCUUGGAAAUUCUGGAGAAGGAGUCUCAUGCACCACCUAUCACACUCCCUCACAUCCUGUUUCUGACUUUGGAAUGGACUCAGGAAAACUAGGCCCCUCUUUAAACCGUGUGAUGUAUUUGAAUGUCUGUUAUUUCCAGCCACCCUAACAUUCUUCUUCCUGUGUGGAUGCUUAUUUGUCAAUCAGUAAAUUUGUUCGUAAAGAAAAUUACUUCUGGUAUUUAGGCUGUGAAUGUACCUUGAAGGGGAGAGUUCAUGGAGAGAGCAUGUGUUCUCUGAUUGUGAGGUCACUGUGAAUGAUUAAAUUGGUAAGGGUAAAGUA